GAGAGACAGAGCACAAUACAAUUAUUUUCUUCAAUUCUAAGUAUUCCUCCAGCUACUGCAGCUAAACUUUUCUCUUUAUAGACAGGCUUUUUAUGAAAAAGUUUAUACUCCUGACUUUAUUUUCUCAUCUCUGAAUUCAGUCGGCCUUCUCCACCUAAAACUUCACUCUUGUCUUCUUCCUGGGACCUUUCUCAAUUCUGAUUUUGCUUGACCUUUUCCUAGCACUUGAUGUUAUUGAACAUUUCCUUAUAUUUUGGCUUUUAUAACAUUGCACUUUUCCCAUUAUAUACCAAUAUGUCAGGUCAUUUCAUGUCAGUCAUUUUUGUGGAAUUUGUCCAUUUUUACAUAUUGGACAUCGUAAUGAUGUCCUUCACACUUUCUUCUGCUGCUUCCUACACUUACAUUGGAUUAUCAAAAUUCCCAUGACUAAUUUCCACUGUAUGCUGAUGAUUCCCAAAUCUUUAUCUCCAUUCCAUAUCUCUAUCCUGUGUUUCAUGUUGCAGUGCUCCAAACAUUUCAAACUUAACAUGUUGAAAUCUGAACAAACAAUUUUCCAAAACCCAUAUUUCCUCUUGUCUUCUCUAGCACAGUGAAUGACAAUAGCAACCACCUGGAAGUUCGAGACAGAUACCUUAGAGUCAUCUUGUCUAUUAGACUAGUUACCAAUUCUUUCCAUUCCUUUAUGCCCGUUAUUACUCACUGGCAAAUAAAAUGCCACGUUUUUAAAAUUCUACCAUCAAAACAUGUUACAUUUAUCACCUUUAUCCAUUCUCAUUGCCAUGUUUUCUGCCUUUUUCUAAAGUACAUACCACUCUCAAAUACGGGCAUUAUUGCCUCAGUCUCCUCAAGGUACCCAUUCUUAAUCCAUUCUUAACACGUUCUUCCCUAUUGAAACCGUUACGUGUGAUUGCUUUUAGAAUGACUUUUAAAAAUAAAAUCUGGCCAUGUCGCUUGCCUGCUUAAAAUUCAUUGUUCAUAAAUCAAAGUUCAGGCUUUUUAAUGUGGCUGCAGACCUCUGUUUAGUUGGUCCCCUACUUACGUCUGAUCAUUUCUCAAUCCUUGUUUUAUAUACUUUAGAAGCAGCCAUGCAAGAGUUUCACUUCCUUAAACACAGUGGUUGUGUUUGUGGUGCACUCCCCCGUCCCAGUUGUCCUUCCAUUAGUCUCAUCUUUCCAUUUUCAGAUAGGUACCAAGUUUUUUUCAGCCUUUCUUAAAAAGACACACUGAACCGUUCCCACUCUGUAUACUUCACCAUCUAAAAUCUUACUGCUUUGUAAUUGCCUGCUUUUCUAUCUUUAUCUGCCAUGAAUUAUAUUGUUCAUGGAUUAUAUGCUUUGCAAGGGCAGAAAUCUUAUCAAUUUUAUCUAUUAUUGUAUUCCCAGUACUUGGAAUGCUGGCAGGCACAAUAAAUGGUAAAUAAAUGUUUCUUGAGUGAAUUAACAAAAAUAGGAUGUGUGCCAUAAGAAAACUAUAAUUAAGAAUAUUUACUCCAGUUGGAGGGAAUAUUAAUAUCUAAUAUGUAAAGUAUUCUCAUAAACAUGUUAUGCAAUACUAAGAACAACUCUCUGAGUAGGAAGGACUAUUGUUUUAUGCAUGAAAGAACCAAAACAGAAAGUUUGGGAUUUGUCCAAGGUCAGAAAGAAAGGGAUUUUUAAAAAUGCAAUUAGGAUAACCUCUAACCUCUGCUUCAGUUUUGCUUUUUCUGUCCCACACUGGCUAAAAUUUUAAAGUGCUGAAGUAUAAAAUUUGCAUAUUUUUUAAUCAGACACAAGAUUAUAUGAUGCCUAGCAGAUUACAACUAACAAUAAAACAAGAAUAAUAGUUACCGCUUAUUGGAUGUUUGCUAUGUUACUUACUAGCUGUCCGUUAACUGUUGUUAGCUUGACUAUUUGUUUUGUUUUUAAAUUUUUAAUUUUUAGUUUUCAAAUUGACAUAAUCAUUGUACAUAUUUUUGGGGCACAUAGUGGUUUCAAUACAUAUAAUAGUGAUCAGAUCAGGAUAAUUAGCAUAUCCGUCACCUUAUACAUUCAUUAUUUCUUUGUGUUGGGAACAUUCAAUAUCAUCCUUCUAGCUAUUAGAAAAUAUAUAAUAUAUUAUUGUUAACUAUAGUCAUUUUACGGUGGAACAGAUCACUAGAAUGCAUUCCUCCUAUCUAGUUAUAAUUUUGCAUCCUUGAAGAAAUCUCUCUGCAUUCCUCCCUUCCCUCUUCCCUUCCCAACCUUUAGUGUCCUCUGUUCUACUUUUUACUUCUAUGAGAUCAACUUUUUUAGCUAAAAAACUUGACUAUUUGAAAAGAGCUACUUUUGACUCCACUCACUUAGAUACUAUCCCCAAAUGUAUUUGUGUUUAUAAUGAAAACAGUAAACACAUGCUACACUUCUGUGAAUAUGAAAUGUCUAGUAUUUCAGUUAGCUAAUUUAUGACUAUUCUUUAAGCUUCAUUGUAAUUCAUCUUCAGUCUUACAGUGGAGAAAUCCUCAUGCUGUGGAAAUUGUCAGAUUUCUGUGGUUUUAUUGUUUAACCAAGUAGCUUUUUUUGAGAGUUGGAAGUAGGGGUGGGGGUAUGGAUAUAAAUUUUCAAAUUGUACAGGCACUAGAUAGUUGAGAGUUGUCACCCAGAAAUUGCUAAAAGUAGGAAUUUAAAAACAUCUUUGAGUUCAUUUUUUUCUUCAUCUUUUAUUCUCUUGAUACUUCACUUGCAAAUGGAUAUGAAAACUUGUUUGGGGAGAUAUUUAUUUGCAUAAAGAAUAUUGGUGCAGUCCUUUAACUUUCAUUAUUUUAUAAAACCAGAUUGUAAUUCUUACCUUCCUAUUUAUAGCAUGUGUGGGAAGUAUAUUUUAUUAUAAAGGGGACAGGCUGAAGACCAUCUUUGUUUCCGGUUGGGGCAUUUCCAGAUUGGAUAAAAUCGAAGGAGAGCCAUCUGUUGAACAUUUAGUAUUCAGAACUGUAGAACUACUCCUGGCAUCUGAGUUUGCCAAGUCCUAGCUAAAAAUAUAUAUUAAAUGGGGUUUGCUUCCUUUUUUUAUUGGUUUUGAACUCUUCUGGCAGAGGUUGUAUAUUCCCUAAGGAGAGAAAUGUGAGAAAAAAAAUGUAGACAUUUAUUUUUCAUUUUCAUUCACAAAACAUUUGGUUGAAAUAUUAACAUCAAAUAUGCCCAGACAUUUCUACUUUCAUUUCUAUGUCUCUCCUGUAAGUUUUUUUAGAAGUUGUUAUUAAAUAAUGAUUACCAAUUCAUUGAUUUUGUGUAUGUCAUAAACACACACACACACACUCUCAUACACACACAGAGACACCCCUGUCUGUAGUCACAUAUUAAGUUGCAAUUUUAUGAUAAUGUAAUAAAAUUGUUAAAUUAUACUAUUUCGCCAGCUCUUGGGAAAGUAUUUUUUUUUGCAUGUAACUCAUCAUCAUUUACAUGCGAAAAAAGAAACAAACAAAAUAUUUUUAUAUAGGUUAAUAAAUAUUAAUAUUCUAUCCACAGAUAUUAAUUAAUGAAUGUCUUCUCUCAUGGAGCCAAGGGACCAGUAUACCAAAAUCAAAACAAACAAACAAACAAAAACAAAGAAAAUAACAACAGAGAUUUGUUAUAUUUCUGUUUAUUUAGAACCUACCCAAAUACCAAACUCUAUUUACAGCUUAUUGUUAUUAGCCAUCAUACAUCUUGUAAAAAAUUUGAGAAGCUCACAUUCUUUAAUAAUAAUCAUUCUGGGACAGCAAACUAGUGUUUAAGGGAAGAAUCAACUAUUUUAAUAAUUGGCUCUGGUUUGCCUGGCAAAAUAUUACAUCAAAACUGUUUGUUUGUGAAUUAUGGAAGGGAGGUUUUAAUACAAAGGAAUGUCAGUAGGCCCCACCCUGGCCAGUCUUUAACAACAGGAUGAGAGGCAAAACAUUUGUCCUGACAAUACAGCAUUGUGAAAAAUAUUUGACUUAUGCACAUGCCAAAACUAAAGAUUCUUUCCUCUUUAGGAAAUAAAUAAAUAAAUCUCUUCACCCUCAAAAGAAAUGUUUUUGAUAAAUGCCAAGAAUAAAGAAGGCAGAAGGAAAUUGUAAAGAAAAUGAGGGAAACAACUGAGUAGUUGAGAGUGAUUGUGUGGUAAACAGUGAUCAGCUGUUUGCACUCAGAGGGGCAAGAAUGACAGUUCAGUUAUUUCUAGAUGCGCGGAGGUAUACACUCUUUUCCAAGAGUCAGGAUAAAUCAGUGAGCCUUAAAGUAGUAGAUUCCGUUGUUGAAUUGAAUAGUGAAUAGCUUUGUUGGUUUUCAGGGACAUAUGGCUAUUUUAUUCUGAAUUAAUGCAUAUUACCUUAACUGUUUUCUUUUUUUAAUGCAUUUUAAAAUGAUAGAGCUCAUAUAAUUGUGAAUGUUUGAAUACAGAAGAAAAAAAAGGCCUAGAGCACUAGGGAAAGCUUUAAGAAAUCAAUUAACAGAGCAAUAUGAAAUUAUAAUUAACUAAAUGAAAACUUUUUAAGGAGAUAAAUAACUUUCCUUUGUAUCUUUAUGUCAUUUUAUUUAGAUAAUUAAUGAAAAUGGCAUCUUUGUUCCUUUGGGUCUUCCUUUUUGUUAGAGAAAAUAUUUUUACUCUGUGGCAGUUAAUUAUGCUAUAUCAACUGAAGAUAAAGCUAAAAAGAAGCCAUCGUGAAAACCAUUAAGGGAAAAAUGACAAAAUGAAUGGAAAAAUGGAAUGGCUGCCUAUACAUGAGACUGAUAAGUGAAAUGUAGUGACAUGAUACAAAGAACACAAACAUAUAUUUAUGUUUGGUUCAAAGUUAGGCUUUUCACACCACUUUCUGUCCUCCUUUGAGCUGUGGGAGUAUUCAGUUCAUAAUAGACUCACAGCGUCUCAUUACUACUUAGAACUUAGUUAACAUUGCCUUCCUGAUGUAAUACAAUGCCCGGAAUUCGAUAAUCGUUCCUGAAAAAAACAAACAAACAAAAAAAAUCACCAUUCCUUUUAAUAGCUUGAGCCUGUACCAGAAUGAUAAGUGGAAAUUAGUCCUCAAAGUAACCUCAGCUGUUUCAUUAUUGUGUGCCUCGAGCAUCUGGUUAUUCAAGGUGAGGCUUCCAUGUUCAAGUAUGAAUCCCUUGGGAUCUGCCGCAGGACUCACGGUAGUGCUGCCUGCUUCUCCCACUCUGUGGCUGACUCCCCUGAGGUAGCAUUCUGCCAGGCAAAGCUGCCUUUCCUUCCUCCUACUACUGUGACUUCAGAAGCUCCUCCCACGGUUCGUAUUGUGCACUCAGGCUUGGCCUGUAACAUUGAAGAGGAGCGCUACUCCGAAAGGGUCUACACUAUCCGGGAAGGAGAAACCCUUGAGUUGACUUGUCUAGUCACAGGACAUCCACGUCCACAGAUCAGGUGGACCAAAACAGCAGGAAGUGCCUCUGACAGAUUCCAAGACUCAAGUGUCUUCAAUGAGACUUUGAGGAUUACAAAUAUUCAGCGACACCAAGGAGGCCGGUAUUACUGUAAAGCAGAGAAUGGCUUGGGGUCUCCAGCGAUAAAGUCAAUCAGAGUGGAUGUAUACUAUUUGGAUGAUCCAGUAGUAACUGUUCAUCAAAGUAUAGGUGAAGCUAAAGAACAAUUUUACUAUGAGAGAACAGUGUUCCUCCGGUGUGUUGCCAAUUCCAAUCCUCCUGUUCGGUAUAGCUGGAGACGUGGCCAGGAGGUCUUGCUGCAAGGAUCUGAUAAAGGAGUUGAGAUUUAUGAACCAUUCUUUACCCAGGGUGAAACAAAGAUCUUAAAACUAAAGAAUCUUCGACCUCAGGACUAUGCUAAUUAUAGCUGCAUUGCUUCAGUGAGGAAUGUAUGUAAUAUUCCUGAUAAGAUGGUGUCGUUUAGACUGUCCAAUAAAACAGCAUCACCGUCAAUUAAACUCUUGGUGGAUGAUCCUAUAGUUGUAAAUCCUGGAGAGGCCAUAACAUUAGUAUGUGUUACAACAGGAGGAGAGCCUGCACCUUCUCUCACCUGGGUCAGGUCCUUUGGGACUCUGCCUGAAAAGACUGUUUUGAAUGGAGGAACUUUGACCAUACCUGCCAUCACCUCAGAUGAUGCUGGUACUUACAGCUGCAUUGCCAAUAAUAAUGUGGGAAACCCUGCAAAAAAGUCCACCAACAUCAUUGUGAGAGCAUUAAAAAAAGGACGAUUUUGGAUCACACCAGAUCCUUAUCACAAAGAUGACAACAUCCAGAUUGGCCGUGAGGUGAAAAUAUCUUGCCAAGUAGAAGCUGUUCCUUCUGAGGAGCUAACAUUUAGUUGGUUUAAAAAUGGUCGUCCAUUAAGAAGUUCUGAGCGGAUGGUCAUUACACAGACUGAUCCUGAUGUCUCUCCGGGAACAACAAACUUGGACAUCAUUGAUUUAAAAUUCACGGAUUUUGGGACGUACACAUGUGUAGCAUCUCUGAAGGGAGGAGGAAUAUCUGAUAUCAGUAUCGAUGUUAAUAUAUCCAGCAGCACAGUUCCACCCAAUCUGACUGUUCCACAGGAAAAAUCACCAUUGGUCACCAGAGAAGGAGACACAAUAGAACUGCAAUGUCAAGUAACUGGCAAACCUAAACCAAUCAUCCUUUGGUCUAGAGCGGAUAAAGAAGUUGCAAUGCCUGAUGGAUCAAUGCAAAUGGAGAGUUAUGAUGGAACACUGAGGAUUGUGAAUGUAUCUAGGGAAAUGUCAGGAAUGUACAGAUGUCAGACCAGCCAAUACAAUGGAUUUAACGUGAAACCAAGGGAAGCCUUGGUGCAGCUCAUCGUUCAGUAUCCCCCUGCAGUGGAACCAGCAUUCUUGGAAAUCCGGCAAGGACAGGAUCGAAGUGUCACUAUGAGUUGCAGAGUACUGAGAGCCUAUCCAAUACGGGUGCUGACCUAUGAGUGGCGCUUGGGCAAUAAAUUAUUACGGACGGGUCAAUUUGACUCUCAGGAAUACACAGAGUACGCUGUGAAGAGUCUUUCCAAUGAAAACUAUGGGGUUUAUAACUGUAGCAUCAUAAAUGAAGCUGGAGCUGGGAGAUGCAGCUUUCUUGUUACAGGAAAGGCCUAUGCUCCAGAAUUCUAUUAUGAUACCUACAAUCCAGUAUGGCAGAACAGACACCGUGUUUAUUCUUACAGUCUACAGUGGACACAGAUGAAUCCUGAUGCAGUGGAUCGGAUUGUUGCAUACCGGUUGGGCAUCAGGCAGGCUGGACAGCAGCGCUGGUGGGAGCAGGAGAUUAAAAUAAAUGGGAAUAUUCAAAAGGGAGAAUUAAUUACAUAUAACUUGACAGAGCUAAUUAAACCAGAAGCUUAUGAAGUCCGACUGACUCCUCUCACCAAAUUUGGUGAAGGAGAUUCAACAAUUCGUGUGAUCAAAUAUAGUGCUCCUGUAAAUCCUCAUUUGAGAGAAUUUCAUUGUGGAUUUGAAGAUGGUAAUAUUUGUUUGUUCACUCAAGAUGAUACAGAUAAUUUUGACUGGACAAAGCAAAGUACAGCAACAAGAAAUACAAAAUAUACUCCUAAUACAGGACCUAAUGCUGACCGUAGUGGCUCCAAAGAAGGUUUUUAUAUGUACAUUGAGACAUCACGACCCAGAUUGGAAGGCGAAAAGGCUCGACUUCUCAGCCCUGUUUUCAGCAUAGCUCCCAAAAACCCUUAUGGACCCACAAACACUGCAUAUUGUUUCAGCUUCUUUUAUCACAUGUAUGGACAACAUAUAGGUGUCUUAAAUGUUUAUCUACGUUUGAAAGGGCAAACAACAAUAGAGAAUCCACUGUGGUCUUCAAGUGGGAAUAAAGGACAAAGAUGGAAUGAGGCUCAUGUUAAUAUAUACCCAAUUACUUCAUUUCAGCUCAUUUUUGAAGGUAUCCGAGGUCCUGGAAUAGAAGGUGACAUUGCUAUUGAUGAUGUAUCAAUUGCAGAAGGAGAAUGUGCAAAACAAGACCUAGCAACUAAGAAUUCCGUUGAUGGUGCUGUUGGGAUUUUGGUUCAUAUAUGGCUUUUUCCCAUUAUCGUCCUCAUCUCUAUCUUAAGUCCUCGAAGGUGACCUUAUCCUGGCAGAGGCUAUAAAAGAUUCACCAGGCACUGGCAUGAAGAAAGAGUCUUUGUAAAUGGACAUUGAACAAACAAACUACCAAAGAUUCCUCCACUGACUACUGACUCAAAAAUAAAAUAAUAAAAACAAAUUUUUUUAAGCACUGGGGAUAAAAAGACAUCAUGGAAGUAUAACUUAUUCCAGACUAAACAUAAAAGAUAAUCUUGACCUGAGUAGAGAAGAGACCUUCAGGUGCUUUUGUGGCUAAAAAGAUUACAGCGUCAUCUGGUUGAACUCUGGAAAAAAAAAAAAAAAUGAAAAAAAGAAAAAAAAAAGAGCUAUAGAAAUCCUUGUCAAAGCACAAAGUCAUGGCUGGUUUUGUUUCAAAUGAAUAGUUUGCUUGUUACCAUGGAAACCUAAUGGCCUGCCAACAAAAACCUCACUGUAAACAGGGUACGUGAAGAGCUGGCAUUUAUUUUCCUUACGAGAAGGUUUUCGUAGAGAAUUAAAUAAAUGUAGGCCCUUUUACCUUUGGCUGUUACCCUUCCUUGAAAAUAACCCGAACUCAGAAUUAUUUAAAGCAUUCAUGUUUCUCCCCACCUUAUCCCCAUCCCACCUUUAUUAUUAUUAUUUUUCUCCCAUGGCUAAGCUAGAUAACUGUAUGCUGUCUCUUUUUGCAUGCACUACUAUCCAGGAUGGUAAACCUGGGCUUACAUGUUACACAGGCUUAUCGGAGUUUGCUUGCGGCCACUUGAACACCCAAACUACGUCAUCUGUUCCAAUGAAGAAACCAAACCACCAUCUUUUAUAAAUUGCCAUGGAAACCAAGUGCCUUCAAUGAAACAAGCCUGAAUAAUUUUCAACUCAGAAGCUUGCACUGCUAAGAGUGGUUUGUGUAAAACUAUUUUAUAAACAAACUACAGAGCCUAAAUGUGCAAAUUACAGGCAAGACAACAAAGCCGCUUCUGAAGAAGAAAGGACCGAAGCUGCUGCGUAAGCCCAUGCAGACAAGAUAUUUGUUGUUUAACCUCCUAGACAGCCAUGGCCUUUCGGCUUAUUGUCCAUUAGAAAAUCACUUCCAUUGAGACCAGACAUGGAGCAACACUUUUUUUCUUCCAGGUUAUUAAAUGGGUCAACCAGAGCAAAAGGUUAUUAAGAAUACUUAGUGCAGAAGGUGGUAAAACACAAAAGUGAUUUUUUUACUCUAACCUCCAUUUGAAAUGAAAUUGGCCCUAGCUUUAGAGGGAACAAGAAAAUGUUUGGGAUUGCAGUGCAUACUAACUCUACAGUGGAACUGGGCCUGAAAAAUCUGGCUUUAUUCUAAACUCUGAGGGUAAUAUGCCUCUGCCCUUUAGUCAGACUCUGUGCAAAUUGUGAAAUAUUAUUUUAUUAUUUUACCAAGAUUAUAAAAACACUUUUACAAAAAAACAAAAACCUGUAAAAAUAAUUUUGAGCUACCUGACGACAAAUCAUAUCUUUAACCAGCCAGUUUUCCAAUGCAUUGUAAAUUUCACUUAAACCUGUUGGUUAUGAAAAUUUGAAGAUCAUUUUCCUUAAAUUAUCUCAGCUUUUAACUUCAUUUAAAAAGACUUUUGUCUAAGAAGAAUAUUAUUAUUAUAUGUUCUUUCAACACCCCAGGAUUAAAAAAACUGAUUAUGCAAGCAAUUGGAAUAUAAGUAUUAAAUUAUAGCAUUUGCAAAUAUUAAUAUAAAAGCACAACAAAAUGUAGUGGAAAAUGACAAAGCUUGUUUUUUAAAACAAUUCUGUAGAAAUGUUUGUGCAAAUUCAGUAAUUCAACUUAAAAUAUAAUUUUACAGCUAUGUUCAAUAAAGCCUCUUUCCAGGUAAGGUAUGACAAGCAGUAUGUGUGUUUGUUGAGCAAUGUUCACUUAUCACUAAAAUGAAAUUAGUUAUACAAUUUAUUGGUUACCAUGGGAUAAAUCUUCAGUGCUCCACAUACCUUAAUGUCUGCAGAAAGAAAUUUUAAUAGGAACUCCCUGAUGCACUCCCCUAUAUUGUAAUACAUGCAGAAAGCAGUUAAACCUUUGAAGGUAAAAUAUGAAACAUAUAUGAACCUGGAAUUUAAUGUCUAUUUUCAGUCAGUUCAAAAGGGGACCAGUUUGAAUAUUUAGGUAGUGAUGGAAUUGAUCUGAACCAAGUCCUUUAAAUUAAACAUAAUAAACAAAUGAGUUUCAUAACUUAUUUGAAUGAAUUAGACAUCUUAAAAUUUUUUCAGAGUUUCACAGUAACCCAUAUACUUUAUCAGACCAAAGAGAUUCAAGUACACAAUAUCUGGGGCAUUUCUUUUACGUUUUACAAAA